UUGCAGGGGCUGUUACAACCUUCUCCUGAAGGCAGGGAUUCUCUCUGCUUCCCCGUGGCCCUCCUGUCUGGUCGGGGACUUCCUUCAGAUGCCGGGAAGAGGCCUCAAGCUGUAUGGGACUGGGCUGGGGUCUGGACACUUGGAGUCUAGGCGUCCCCUGGCUUGGGGCUGCGUUUCUAUGAUGGUGACCAAGUUCCCUAUCUUUCCUCUUGGAGGUGGUCUGGGCCGUGAUGGCCAAGCCUCUGUCAGUGGGCUACGUUCACGGCACAUAAGUUGAGUAUGCUGGCAGCAGAGGCUGACUGUUAAGACCAGCAGCAGCCCCUUGCUGGCGGAGACUCUGGCUGUCUCUCCAAGGAAGGAAUGUUCUGGUCGCUUCUGGAGGUGGCACCUUUCAGAACAGGGGGCCCAAGUACCCAGGGCUCCCGGGCCCCUGGGGGUCCUGUGGGUGGGGAUCUGACUCCUGCGGCCAUGGACUGUGGGCGCAGACCCUGGGCUUAGUUCAGCUCCUGAUGGCUCCCCGUUGUCUGCGGCGAUCUGGUUGCUCUGGUUGUCUGGGGAUCGGUGCGCCUGUCUAAACCUGCUGACAGGUGGGAAAGUGAACUUGACAGGGAGUCCCAGGGCCAAAUGGGUCUCCCAGUGGGGAGGAGUGGGUGCGGUCUGAGGUAUGUCCAGCUCUACCCGUGGCCUCUCUGGGCAUCAGGGUCCCUGGUGAUGGAGCCCAACCUUUGUGCACUGAUCUUCCCAGCUGUUGACAGGCCCUGAGGAGGCAUGGAAGGUGAGGCCGAGGCAGGCGACCGUCAGAUCUGCCUCGGCCUGGCAGUGGCCCCUGCCUGCGCUUCCUCCUGCCUGGCCGGCUGUUUUCAUCCUGGCCCUUUGAGAACUUCUAGGGUCCUGGCUGCCUCCAAUGGAGGGUGCUGGUCCCAUCUUCUUCCCAGCUGUGCCCUGCCGUGGAGCUCCGGAAACCUCGAGGUUCCCCUAACCCUUCCCCCUCUUCCCUGCGGCCCCCAUUGCAAGCCCACCAGCCUCUGCCUCUUAAGGGCUUCCCUGCCAUCACCUAUGUUCCUUUGUCACAGACAUGAGUGUGUAGAGGUGUCAAGACGGGACCCCAGAUGAUGCUGAUGGCUUUGCCUAAGUGGCCUGGGGAGGGUCUCUCUCUCUGGUCCCUGAAGGCCACCUUUUUCCUAAGCCUGUGUGUCAGGUUGGGGGCGGUUCAGGGAGCACUUCCAGCCUGAGUGGUCUCUGAUACGUGAAGACUGAAUGCUGAGAGCCUGGGGCAGAUUUUCCUAGGGGUCCCUGGACCCCCAAAGCUGGCCCCACAUCGAGGGAUGCUCUGAGCCCCUGCUGGAGGGUUGGAGGAGACUUCUCAAAUCCAGACCCUCUGCAGACCCCCUGCCACCCUCCCAAGCCGGCCCUGUGGCGAGGCACAAUUGUCCAACUGUCAGCCCAGUGCAGAUGGGACGGCGACCCCGCCCCACAAGGCUGCUCAGCUGCCCUCUGCAUGCGCUGCAUCCCCACCCCACCUGAGCAGCAGAUGGCCUUUCCACGUGCACUCUGCCAGGCCUGGCCUCCGGGAGCAGAGGUCAGCUGAUACAGACGUGAGGUGCACCUGUGGGGGACCAGGGCCAGGUCCUGGCCUCACGGGGUUGGCUUGGUGUGGGCGUCUGACACACUUGUUUAUGGCAGUUCACUUUUGACUUACUUGAAGGAGAACUUUACACCGAGGCCUUAAUGGAAAACCAGGGCCACGUGGCACCUGGAGACAUGAUUCUGAUAAGUGGACAGGCUUUUGCCCCGCAGCUGAAAGGCACGAUUUGUGGUGGUGAGACGUGCCCUUGCCCGCACCGGAGGAGCCUUUCUCCUGGGCAGAAUCAGGACUGAAAGAGACACGCCCUCGAGUGUGCUUCGUGCUGCUGCUGCUCCACCACGUGCCCUGGCCGUGUGGGGCGGGGGUGCUGGCGGGAUGGUCCCCAAGGUUGGGUGCAUGUUGCCUCGUGGAUGAAGUCCUGUGGUCUGGGGUGCUCCAUCUGGAACGUGUCAGGUCCACUCAUGGCUCCUGCCAGCUGCUUUCGUCUAGGGCACAGCGUCACCUUCGUCCCCUCCGGAGCUGCACGUGGCCUGAGCAGGAUGGUGCCCUCCAGCCCAGCGGUGGAGAAGCAGGUGCCCGUGGAACCUGGGCCUGACCCCGAGCUCCGGUCCUGGCGGCACCUCGUGUGCUACCUUUGCUUCUACGGCUUCAUGGCGCAGAUACGGCCAGGGGAGAGCUUCAUCACCCCCUACCUCCUGGGGCCCGACAAGAACUUCACGCGGGAGCAGGUCACGAACGAGAUCACGCCGGUGCUGUCGUACUCCUACCUGGCCGUGCUGGUGCCCGUGUUCCUGCUCACCGACUACCUGCGCUACACGCCGGUGCUGCUGCUGCAGGGGCUCAGCUUCGUGUCGGUGUGGCUGCUGCUGCUGCUGGGCCACUCGGUGGCGCACAUGCAGCUCAUGGAGCUCUUCUACAGCGUCACCAUGGCCGCGCGCAUCGCCUAUUCCUCCUACAUCUUCUCUCUCGUGCGGCCCGCGCGCUACCAGCGUGUGGCCGGCUACUCGCGCGCUGCGGUGCUGCUGGGCGUGUUCACCAGCUCCGUGCUGGGCCAGCUGCUGGUCACUGUGGGCCGAGUCUCCUUCUCCACGCUCAACUACAUCUCGCUGGCCUUCCUCACCUUCAGCGUGGUCCUCGCCCUCUUCCUGAAGCGCCCCAAGCGCAGCCUCUUCUUCAACCGCGACGACCGGGGGCGGUGCGAAACCUCGGCUUCGGAGCUGGAGCGCAUGAAUCCUGGCCCAGGCGGGAAGCUGGGACACGCCCUGCGGGUGGCCUGUGGGGACUCAGUGCUGGCGCGGAUGCUGCGGGAGCUGGGGGACAGCCUGCGGCGGCCGCAGCUGCGCCUGUGGUCCCUCUGGUGGGUCUUCAACUCGGCCGGCUACUACCUGGUGGUCUACUACGUGCACAUCCUGUGGAACGAGGUGGACCCCACCACCAACAGUGCGCGGGUCUACAACGGCGCGGCAGAUGCUGCCUCCACGCUGCUGGGCGCCAUCACGUCCUUCGCCGCGGGCUUCGUGAAGAUCCGCUGGGCGCGCUGGUCCAAGCUGCUCAUCGCGGGCGUCACGGCCACGCAGGCGGGGCUGGUCUUCCUUCUGGCGCACACGCGCCACCCGAGCAGCAUCUGGCUGUGCUAUGCGGCCUUCGUGCUGUUCCGCGGCUCCUACCAGUUCCUCGUGCCCAUCGCCACCUUUCAGAUUGCAUCUUCUCUGUCUAAAGAGCUCUGUGCCCUGGUCUUCGGGGUCAACACGUUCUUUGCCACCAUCGUCAAGACCAUCAUCACUUUCAUUGUCUCGGACGUGCGGGGCCUGGGCCUCCCGGUCCGCAAGCAGUUCCAGUUAUACUCCGUGUACUUCCUGAUCCUGUCCAUCAUCUACUUCUUGGGGGCCAUGCUGGAUGGCCUGCGGCACUGCCAGCGGGGCCACCACCCGCGGCAGCCCCCGGCCCAGGGCCUGAGGAGUGCCGCGGAGGAGAAGGCAGCACAGGCACUGAGCGUGCAGGACAAGGGCCUCGGAGGCCUGCAGCCAGCCCAGAGCCCGCCGCUUUCCCCAGAAGACAGCCUGGGGGCUGUGGGGCCAGCCUCCCUGGAGCAGAGACAGAGCGACCCAUACCUGGCCCAGGCCCCGGCCCCGCAGGCAGCUGAAUUCCUGAGCCCAGUGACAACCCCUUCCCCCUGCACUCUGUGCUCCGCCCAAGCCUCAGGCCCUGAGGCUGCAGAUGAGACUUGUCCCCAGCUGGCUGUCCAUCCUCCUGGUGUCAGCAAGCUGGGUUUGCAGUGUCUUCCAAGCGACGGUGUUCAGAAUGUGAACCAGUGACUCUCGGGCGCCCCUGUGGUAACUUUGCAGGCGGCCCUCAGUGCAUCCCCACGACCCCUGCCUCGAGGGCCGCCUGCCUUAGCAAUGGGGGCCUCCGCUUAUCCUGCUAGCAGGCCCCCUAGGAUUCCCCCUGCCCUGUGCCGCACUCUGGCGGUGGCCACAGCGUGCUGGCGACACUCAGGGCAGCUGCCUGGCCAUGCUGUCCCUGCACUGUGCCCCGCGGGCUUUGUUGCUGGAAGAGGUGGGUGGUGGGCUUCUGCGUCCACCAGGCCUCACUGGCUCAUGCCCCUUGGGGGGCUUGAGACAAAUCCUUUCUGCCCCCCAGGGCUAGUGAAGUGGCCUCUUGGAUACCAGCUCAGGGGACACUGGCCCCACAGGAGUUGUGAGCCCUCUAGGGCAGGGUGGGAGCCGGGACCCUCAGGUGUAGCUGAGCUGUGACAUUGCUGGUCAUCCUUGGUGCUCUUGCUUUUUUGAAAGAUGCUUUUUUUUUUUUUAACUGACGUAGAAUGAAGAACUGCAUGUGGCUUCUCUGUCUCUGUGGAAAAGCCAUCUCAGGUUGGCGGCAGACACAUUGUCAUCAGAGGGGAGCAGCGGCUCUGGUCCUCGGAGCUGGUUCCUCUCUCCCACCCUAAGGGCAGCCCUCCAUGGUCCUGUCUGUCCUUCUGAAGUGUGUCCAUCCUGACCUGCGGGUCCUCAGCUGCUCCCACACUUGUGCCAGCCCGGAGGGGACUGGUCCCGGUCACCGCGGACGUGCUGGCCUUGGUAUGUGCCAGGCUUGCCUGGGCUGGGCAGCCUUGGGGGGGCUGCCUUUGUGGUGGGCGCUGGGGAAGUACGUCCCAGCGGCCUCAGGGUCUAAGGAGCGCUAGUGCCUUGCCCACAGGUGCGGGACCAUCUGAUGUGAUGUGAAUACUCUUCCCACAUACAUUAAACACACUUAAGUGAGUGUGCGCAGGGCUUCUGAUUCAGGGCCGGCCUGGCCUGGGGGUUGAGGGUCAGCAGUCAGUGAGGAGGCCAGGAGAGGCGUCCCAGCCUUCUCCCGCCUCCAGCCCACGCAGGGCCUUGGUGCCCAUGAGCUGAGCACCCCCACAACCCUAGUCAACGGCCCUAUCCUGUGGGGCCUCUGCCACAUCUCAGCGGCCCCAGGUGAAUGGCUGGCUGCUCAGCACGGAGAGCUGGGGAGAGAAUCUCUGGCUGGGGAGGGGCUGCUGGAGCUGCUGGACCCAGGGGUCUCCCGAGGUGGCUCAGGGGAGCAGGCAUCUUGGGGUACCCUGGGUUGAGGCAGAGGCUGCACGUGGAAGAUGGCCCGAGUCAGUGGAUGGUGCCAGUCAGACAGGGCCAUGGUCCCAGGUGCAUCCAGGGGCUCUGUCAUGGCCACCCUGGGGACCCUGCUUGGGGGGGGGUCUGCACCAGCCAUUUCCUGGGCUCGUAGAUCUAGCAGGAUGUGAUGGGUGGAGGUGGGCUGGGCCUGUGCCAUGGGCUAGAGCGUCACUGGGGAGGCCCACACCGCCAUCAGAAUCCUCCUCCCAGCGCCUCCCCAACCUGAGGGCCUGCUCCCUCCGCAGCCUGCUCACUGCACCCACUGCCUGCCUGCCUCUGAGUCCUGCACUCACCCGUCCACCAGGACAGGGAUGGCUGUCAGGAUGUAGUGUUGCUGGGAGCAAGUCAGGUCCUGCUGUGAGGAGAGACCUAAGAGUGUUGGUGUGUGUCCACACACCCGUGCAUGCCUGUGUACCUGUGCACACUAUGGAUGCUCCUGCACACCUGUGUACAACUGCACGCCUGUGUAUGGCCAUGCAUGCAUACCCCAUGUAACCGUGCGUGCCUGUGCACACUCGGGAUCUGCCAGUGGGGCAGUCCAGGGAUAAAAGACUCCUGAGAACUCCUUUUGGAGAAUUGUGUCCUUCCUGUGACAGUGAAGGCUGCUUGCAAACCAAGAGUCAGUGUAAAAGGUCACUUUUAUUUGCCUGUCUGAAUUGGCUUCACAUCACACACAAUUACAGAACCAGCCCCACCGGUUUCGUCGCAGUCCUGAGGCAGGUGCGUGUUGGCUGUGCUGUGGUCAGCCUGGCGCUGCCCUGAGUCCACUUGUCCCUCCACAGAACGAAUGACUCGGGUUGAUGUUGCCGGAUCUCAGGGGUGGCUGUGACUGACAGAGGACCUUGUUGCACCUCGUGGCUGCUUUGUUCACCCGCAGGGCGGCCUGUGGGCACCCCGGGGUUCCCCUUCAGUCCCAAGGAGGGUAAGGAUAUGGGUUUCCUAGGAGACAGCCAAUGACUGCCCUGCAUCUGGAGCCAGCCUGUCCAUGGGCAGUGCACAGAUGACAGCCCUCCCUCACUGCCCUGUGUGCUGGCUACCGCAUGUCCUGUGCCAGCCUCAGCCUCUUUGAUGUGGCCGUGUUCCAUCCUGGCGCUCAGCUGGACAAGUGCUGGCUGAGCCACGUCCCAGCCAGGGGCAUGAGAUGGGGGCCCUGGAUGGGAGGCUGCCAGACCCCAACUCAUGGGUCCCUUGAAUCUCCCAGCUUGGACUCGGCCAGGGUGGAGCUGUCUGCUUUGGAUGUAUCAUCUCAUGGCUCAUUUGGGAGGCCAGCCCCAGGCUGCUGUGCUUGGUGUUGGAGGACAGGCCGGAGCUGGGGGUCACAGUGCGCCUCUGAGCUUGGGAACCUGCUUCAGCCUGGGGUUGCUGUGGAGAAUGGCCCAGAGCUGAGCAGAAGGGGCUCCCCCUAGCCCCAGGGACCUGAGCCUCCCUCCCAUCUACCGCAGGGCGAGCACACACCCUGGAGGAGCCCAGAUGGCCUUGUGCUGAGUGUGGCCUCAGCUCCCAUUGCCUCACGGGGCCUGUCUGCUAACAGGUCUGGGUUUUGUGCACAGAACGGUGCUGCUAGGUGGGAGAUGAAGUCAGCACCUGCUGGGGCGAGCACGGCUUCCCAAAGCAGGAAAUCCUGGAGAAAUCGAGCCGUGGUCUGAUCAGGCCAAGAGGUUGCACAGGGCAUGAUACUGCACCCUGCCUGACCCAGCUGGGCUCACAGGUCAGGGGAGAGUUGGGGCAGGUGAAUGUCAGCAUCAGGCUUCUGUUUUAAACUUUUAAAAAAAUACA